GGAGCUGUGGGGACGACUCUUCUGGAGGAAGCAGCGCGGGCUUGACCGGCGUCGGCCCGCCGCCUCCGCUGCCGCUUCGCCCCAAUCCGGUCCCUCUGGCCCGGCCUGACCCGGUCUGGCUUGUUCGGGCUCAGCGGCCGCGAGGCCGCAGCUCCCGAUGGAAAUCAUAUUAUGUAGAAUACUUGGGUGACAUCUGCCUGAGAGAUCUCCAAGAAUUACAGAUUGAGUCUCGCUCUGUUGCCCAGGCUGGAGUGCAGUGGUGCAAUCUCUGCUCACUGCAACCUCCGUCUCCCGAGUUCAAGCAGUUCUCCUGCCUCAGCCUCCUGAGUAGCUGGGAUUACAGGUGCAUGCCAUCAUGCCUAGCUAAUUUUUGUAUUGUUAGUAGAGAUGGGGUUUCACGUGUUAGCCAGGAUGGUCUGGAUCUCCUGACCUCGUGAUCUGCCUGCCUCGGCCUCCCAAAGUGCUGGGAUUACAGGUGUGAGCCACUGCGCCCAGCCUAAUUUUUGUAUUUUUAGUAGAGAUGGGAUUUUGCCAUGUUGGCUAGGCUGGCCUCAAUCUCCUGGCCUCAGGUGAUCUGGCCACCUUGGUCUCCCAAAGUGCCGGGAUUUUUUUUCUUUUUUUCUUUUUUUUUUUUUGAGACGGAGUCUCGCUCUGUCGCCCAGCCUGGAGUGCAGUGGCGCGAUCUCGGCUCACUGCAAGCUCCGCCUCCCGGGUUCACACCAUUCUCCUGCCUCAGCCUCCCCAGUAGUUGGGACUGCAGGCGCCUGCCACUAUGCCCGGCUAAUUUUUUGUAUUUUUAGUAGAGACGGGGUUUCACCAUGUUAGCCAGGAUGGUCUCGAUCUCCCGACCUCGUGAUCCACCUGCCUCGGCCUCCCAAAGUGCUGGGAUUACAGGCAUGAGCCACCGCGCCCAGCUGAUUUCUUUUUUUUUUUUUUUAAAUGUGUUGUAGAGACAUGGUCUCACUAGGUUGUUCAGGUGGAUCUUGACCUCCUGGCCUCAAGGGAUCCUCUCAUCUCAGCCUUCCAAAGUUCUGGGAUUAUAGUUGUGAGCCACACCCUCAGUCUUUGUUUUAGAUUAUGGUUGGUUGUUUUUUUUCAGACAGAUUACCUACUUCAAGUAGACUUUAUAUUUGCUUUUGUAUUUAAUCAAGAUUUGUUUAUAUAAAUUGUUUAUGUACUGUUAAAUCCAAAUGCUCUUACACUUUAAGGUUCUAUUAGUUUUAGAUUUUUUUUUUUUUUUUGAGAUGGAGUCUCACUCUGUUGCCAGGCUGCAGUACAGUGGCGGGAUCUCGGCUCACUGCAACCUCCGACUCCCUCGUUCAAGUGAUUCUCCUGCCUCAGCCACCUGAGUAGCUGGGGAUUACACGCACGCACCACCACGUAUAGCUAAUUUUUGUAUUUUUAGUAGAGAUGGGGUUUCACCACGUUGGCCAGGAUGCUCUUGAUCUCCUGACCUCGUGAUCCACCCGCCUUGGCUUCCCAAAGUGCUGGGAUUACAGGCGUGAGCCACCGCACCUGGCCUAGUUUUAGAUUUAAAUCGCUAGUUGAUAUUGUUCCUUUCAGCUCAUCAGUUGAAAUGGUAGUUGUGUAGAAAAGUUAAUGGGUGUUUGCCACAAUCUUCUGUGAGUUGAAGUUAGGGUUUGUGACUGUUUCACUUUCUCAACUAGUAUUCUCUUUUCGUUUAUAUGUAAUUAAGUAACAUUUCGCUGUUUGCGGGCUUUUCUUUUUUGAGAUGGAGUUUCCCUCGUGUGUGUGUGUGUGUGUGUGUGUAUGUGUGUACGUGUGUGUGUGACGGAGUUUCGCUUUUAUUGCCCAGGCUGGAGUGCAGUGGCGCAAUCUCAGCUCACUAUAACCUCCGCCUCCUGGGUUCAAGCGUUUCUCCUGUCUUAGCCUCCCAAGUAGCUGGGAUUACAGGUGCCUGUCACCACGCCUGCUUAAUUUUUUUGUAUUUUUAGUAGAGACAGGGUUUCACCAUAUUAGCCAGGCUGGUCUCGAACUCCUGACCUCAGGUGACCCACCCAUCUCAGCCUCUCAAAAUUCUGGGAUUACAGGCGUGAGCCACCGCACCCGGCCAAUGGAGUUUCACUCUUGUCAUCCAGGCUAGAGUGCAGUGGCGCAAUCUUGGCUCACUGUAAACUCUGCCUCCCGGGUUAAAGUGAUUCUCCUGCCUCAGCGUCCCGAGUAGCUGGGAUUACAGGUGCAUAUCACCACACCUGGCUAAUUUUGUAUUUUUAGUAGAGAUGGGGUUUCGCCAUGUUGGCCAGUCUGGUCUUGAACUCCUGACCUCAAGUGAUCCACCCACCUUAGCCUCCCACAGUGCUGGGAUUACAGGCAUGAGUCACCACACCCGGCCAGUAGAACUCUUUAAACCUGAAAAAUCAGUCAACUUUGCAGACUAGAGGAGGAUGUUGAACACCUAUGUGUGUUUUUUUUUUCUUUACCAACUAUGCACCUAUUUUUCAGACACCUAAAAGUAAUGUCUGUGAAACAGUGGUUUUCUUUUUCUACAUAUUACAGCAGGAAGUGUUCCUAUUUAUGUACUGUCUGUAUCAAUACUAACGGGGCAUGAUAAGCAAAAUUUUAAACUUUGGUAGUUAAACCUUUAUGUUGCCUCCCCUCUGGGCUGCCAGCUGUGGGGAUGUGCUUCUCCCUUAAGGACUUUGGCAAGAAUAACAAGUUCAUUGGAAUUUGACUUUCUGACAUAGAGCAGACAGCCUUGCCCUGUCAUGCCAGGCCUUUCAUGUGAAGUUACCAUUUAUUAGCUGCUUCUGUCUCUCCAGGGAAGGAUUUCCCUUUUAUAAGCCUGGGCCAGGGGGAUGAUAGUAAGAUUCCCCAUGUGAUACCAGAGUUGGAAUAGGCUGUAGUGAGAUUAGGGCCAGGACUGUCCCAUUUUGAUUCUUGAAUGGUUUCUGUUACAACUUGUCAUGGGGAAAAAGUAACACUUAUUUUUUUUUUCCUCCCUUAGAAGACAAAAAUACUAAUGCAUUUGAGAAAGCGGUAGUUUUGGGGGGAGGGGGAAAAAGCAACUGCUUUCCUGAUCUGCAACUUGGCUGGAUGCUAAGAUGUCAGUGGACAUGAAUAGCCAGGGGUCUGACAGCAAUGAAGAGGACUAUGACCCAAAUUGUGAGGAAGAGGAAGAAGAAGAAGAAGACGACCCUGGGGACAUAGAGGACUAUUACGUGGGAGUAGCCAGCGAUGUGGAGCAGCAGGGGGCUGAUGCCUUUGAUCCCGAGGAGUACCAGUUCACUUGCUUGACCUACAAGGAAUCUGAGGGUGCCCUCAAUGAGCACAUGACCAGCUUAGCUUCUGUCCUAAAGGUAUCUCAUUCAGUUGCUAAACUUAUAUUAGUUAAUUUCCACUGGCAAGUUUCAGAGAUAUUGGACAGAUACAAGUCCAAUUCUGCUCAACUGCUUGUUGAGGCUCGAGUUCAGCCUAAUCCAUCAAAACAUGUUCCCACAUCCCAUCCCCCUCACCACUGUGCAGUGUGUAUGCAGUUUGUGCGAAAGGAAAACCUACUCUCUCUGGCCUGUCAGCACCAGUUUUGCCGCAGCUGCUGGGAGCAGCACUGCUCAGUUCUCGUCAAGGACGGCGUGGGCGUGGGAGUCUCUUGCAUGGCUCAGGACUGUCCACUCCGUACACCAGAGGACUUUGUGUUUCCAUUGCUUCCCAAUGAAGAAUUGAGAGAGAAAUACAGGCGCUACCUCUUCAGGGACUAUGUGGAGAGUCAUUACCAGCUCCAGCUGUGCCCUGGUGCAGACUGCCCCAUGGUUAUUCGGGUACAGGAGCCUAGAGCUCGCCGAGUACAGUGCAAUCGGUGCAACGAGGUCUUCUGUUUCAAGUGUCGUCAGAUGUAUCACGCACCCACAGACUGUGCCACAAUCCGGAAAUGGCUCACGAAGUGUGCAGACGACUCUGAAACAGCCAACUACAUUAGUGCUCACACUAAAGACUGUCCCAAGUGCAACAUCUGCAUUGAGAAGAAUGGAGGCUGCAAUCACAUGCAAUGCUCCAAAUGUAAACACGACUUCUGCUGGAUGUGUCUAGGAGAUUGGAAGACUCAUGGCAGUGAAUACUAUGAGUGCAGUCGUUACAAGGAGAAUCCUGACAUCGUGAACCAGAGCCAACAAGCCCAGGCGAGGGAAGCCCUCAAGAAGUACUUAUUCUACUUUGAGAGGUGGGAAAACCACAAUAAAAGCUUGCAGCUAGAGGCACAGACAUACCAGCGGAUUCACGAGAAGAUUCAGGAGAGGGUCAUGAACAAUCUGGGGACAUGGAUCGACUGGCAGUACCUACAGAAUGCUGCCAAGCUCUUGGCCAAGUGUCGAUACACCCUGCAAUACACCUACCCAUAUGCAUAUUACAUGGAGUCCGGACCCAGGAAGAAGCUGUUUGAAUACCAGCAGGCUCAGCUGGAGGCUGAGAUCGAAAACCUCUCAUGGAAAGUGGAGCGUGCAGACAGCUAUGACAGAGGGGACUUGGAGAACCAGAUGCAUAUAGCGGAGCAGCGGAGGAGAACCCUGCUGAAAGAUUUCCAUGACACCUAAGUUGGGAUGUGGAUGUGCCGGGGUGAGGAAGAUGUGGCUGCAAGGUCUCCCGGCUGCCAUACUGCAUGCUGCAGGCUCUGCCUUUCAUGACCCCAGGCAACAGCCAGGGCCCCACUCCUGAGAGACACUGGCAACACCUCUUAGUUGAUUUCUGUUUUCUUCUCUUUUCACUUUUUGUUUCUACCAGGGUAGAGGCCAUGUUGAACUGGCCUCUUUUCAGGACUUUUAUUUCCCCCUGGAUGGUUGUUGGGAGGGAGGGAAAGUGUUUUCUGAAUGGCUAUUAAUAGUAUUAGAUCAUUACAACUUAUGUAACUUUCAAAGGUUGUACAAUUAUACAAAAAAAAAAAAAAGGCAAACUAUAGGAUAACACAGAGCCCUUUUUGAAAAUAAAUUGGCAUUGGAGUGUUUUACCCUCUAGCUGUUUUACUUAGAAUGUAACAUAUGCUGCCUACCCACCUCAAAAUGUCUGUACUGCAAGAGGGCCCUGGGCCUCUGCUUUCCAUAUUCACGUUUGGCCAGAGUUGUAGUCCCAAAGAAGAGCAUGGGUGGCAGAUGGUAGGGAAUUGAACUGGCCUGUGCAAUGGGCAUGGAGCACAAGGGGUCACAGCAUGCCUCCUGCCUUACCGUGGCAGUACGGAGACAGUCCAGAACAUGGUCUUCUUGCCACGGGGUGUUGUUGUCUCUGGUGGUGCUGCAUGUCUGUGGCUCACCUUUAUUCUUGAAACUGAGGUUUACCUGGAUCUGGCUACUGAGGCUAGAGCCCACAGCAGAAUGGGGUUGGGCCUGUGGCCCCCCAAACUAGGGGGUGUGGGUUCAUCACAGUGUUGCCUUUUGUCUCCUAAAGAUAGGGAUCUACUUUUGAAGGGAAUUGUUCCUCCCAAAUAAAUUUGCUUUACCUUGGUCCUUUCUUUUGUGCCAGUAUUCAAGUGGUAUAGCUCUGAGCAGGGUCACAUUUGGCCAAACCUGACACUGUCUUGCUGCAUUCUCCUUUGGCAAACAUCAGGGUCAGAAUUCAGGAUAGCCCUUCCUAGGGCACUGGACUUUCUGGCAUGGGGGCUGUGUUUGCACAAGUUAUUUUCAUGUUACCUGGAGAGUGUCCAGAGGCUGCUCUGAGGCUGAGGUGUGUUCCCCCUUGCCUGGUUCCAGCUGUCAGAGGGAUACCAUCCUAGGGUCUGGGAAUCCAAGGCCACGAGACUCCUUGGUUUGUGGUCCGAGAUCCUGUACUAAGGAGGGUCUGGCCAGAGGAACAGACCAGCUUUUGCACAAUGAAGCGCAAGGGAACAAGUGGUUUGCCUGGUGUCCUACCUGUCCUGAACCUGGUCCUGUGGGCCAUUGAAAAGUUAGAUCUGUGAUCUCUGGGGUUUUUGUGGCUUUGUUCAAUGCUUCCACUCUAGGGCAGGCAGAGCAGUCUAUACUCUCCCAAGCCUGCUUGACCUCCAAGUAGAGCUGAUACAGAGAUCUGUGAAUAUUGUGAUAGAAAUUCUUUGGUAUUCAUACAUUUCAGCUGCAAGUCAGCAAUUUCCCAGGUACCAUGUAAGCUAUAAAACAGUCAUUCUUAAAGACAGAGGAUAGCUGUGACUCAUGGGAUCAUGAGGUCCAUGGCUGGUUGCAGGUUCCCUUUUUCCUUCCUCAGGUUUUGUCUCUUCCUGUGUUGUCCCCAGCAAGGGAGAGACUGUGGGGUGGAUUGGGAGAACAGAUUAGGAGUAUAGCAAAUGAACCCAGAAUGGAACAGUGGGGAGCUAACUGUGAAUGAGGAGAGUACCUGCUGCAGGACCUGGAGGUCAGGUGUGAAUGCUGUAUUGGCACAGGGAAUAAAUAUCCUGGCGUCUGGAGCCUUCACCUCUCCGUCAAGUCCUUCCUGUGAUACUGCCAUGGCACAGGAUCUGAGUUGCAGCUCUGCACCCUAAAUCACACCCUGGGCAUUGUCUGGGCUGCAGGGCUGCCAGGUUCUGUACUUGUGUCCAGCUGUGGCCCUGGAUGCUGGAGCUGGAGGGUUUUCUGUGCUCAGACUGUAGCCUGUAGCUCUUGGCCUGUGUAGAGCCCCCUCCUGUGCCCUCAGUGGCUGUCGUUUGUUAACAUCAUCAGGAAGAUGGGAAAGGUCAGGCAGAAUUUUUCUGCCCUACAAAGGGUGGAAGAGAAAGGACACAGUAUUUUCAUGAAUUUACCAUAUAUCUUUGUUUUUCUUCAACGAAAAAGUUAAUUGAGGCAAUGUCAUCUGCUCAAAGUUGAGUGGUUUAUUCACAAUAAACUGUAAGUUUCUGAUUAUAAAAAUGUGUCUAGAGUCUUUCUUCAUGGGGUCUAGGUAGUCUUCUGAGCCCACAGGGGUCUGGCCAGUGAACACCAGAGGAGUGCCUUCCUAUCAGUCAGCCCCUUCUUCCAGAGGGCUGUGGAGGCCCCAGUGGCCAAACUCGGCUCUGUUUUCCCUUUCUGGCUGUUGGGGGAGAGGGCACCUGUAAGUGAUCCCUGUGGAAUGAAGUAGAAAAUCCUGCCAGUUUUCCGCUCUCCUCUCCCUCAGUACAGGCUGAAUCAUUCCCCACCACAGAUAGAUCCCAGGGUUGUGGUAGAGUACUGAUAUAAAUGUCCCAACCCCCCCAUUCUGAGACCUCCGGACCCCUCCAAAGCAGACAUGGGAAUGUAGGGCUGUGGAAUAUGGCAGGGUGAACUCCAGCUUCACGGGAGCCCUAAGGGUUAUGAAGAGACAACUUGGGGCAGAAACAAGUGUGGAGUCUAAUCUCAAGGGUGAAGGACAGGAAAUGAGGUUUGGAUUGAUUAAGGGGGUCCACAUUUGUGGUGUCAGAAGUGGCAGUAGUGUCAGUGAUAAGUAGCUCAGGGGUAGAGUGGAGGCUCCAUAGCUGUGGGCAACAUGCACAGGGCACCUGUGGCUAGAAGAGGCCUCAUACAUUGCCAGUCUGAACUCCGCAGCUCUUCCUCUGGACCUCAGGUGUGCCAAGCCCCACGCUUGGCACCUGGGCAUACAGUGGUAUGCAAGUGAUUCACGUGCUCUAGCUUCCAGGAGCUUCCAAUCCAUGGGGAACAUAGAAGGAAUUGAUCACUAGUGAAUGUUUGUUUUUUGUUUUGAGACAGUCUCGCUCUAUCGCCCAGACUGGAGUAC